AGGGCUGGCCCCCUCCACCGCACAGGAAACGGGGCAGGAGGGCGGACCCCCAUCUCAUGUAGGAAUGCCGUGUCCCCAGGGUGAGCCCUCAGGUAAGGGUACCAGUUUCUUCCUGAGCCAUGACCAGAGCCAUUCCCAGAUAAAUGAGGUUUCCUGGAAGGAUGUUACCAGUGCCUUAUCUCUGGCCAACAUGGUGCUGGGGCUCUUCUCCAUCAUCUUCAGCUUCAGCAGGAAAUGCCACUAUGCCUCCCGGAUGCUCCUGGUCAGCUUCCUGUUAGACAUGGCAGUCAGGGCAAUGACCAGCCACAUCAACAUAUGCUCCAAAUUGGGAGCCGAGCUGAAUGACUUUGCCGUCUUCACCACCUUCGGCUUGGCCUCCGCUCUGCUCCUAGGCGUGGAUGGACUUCUGAGUGGGAUCCUGGCCAUCAUCUAUGUGUCAGCUGCUUCUUUCCACUUGUGCUUUUAUUCACCUGGAGUCCCCUCCACAUACAAGGGUCUACCCUGCCCCUAUGCUUCCUGCAUCUUGGCUUCCACCUCCCUUCUGACCAAAGGCAACAGGUUCAUCCUCUGCUGCAUGGCCUCACUCAUGAUUCUCUUCAUGAUGGACCAGAGCUACUAUCCAUAUGACAAAAUCCUGGAGUCUGAGAACUGGAAAAAAUUGGUUUAUAUAGGAGGUGUCAUCAUGCUGUUUUUCUCCCCAUUGUCUCUGUCUGCUUUUUACUGCCUGAUGUGGUCGCUCUCGUACAUCUUCUUUCCAGAUGCUCUGUGGGGCAAGGCAGCCUGUCUUUCGCCACAGCACUGAGGAAGCUAAGCAGCUCUACCAGCUCCUGCCGGCCUCUGUGGGGUUUGUGUCAGCAUAUUGGGUCAAGCCUGCACUAAAGCUUUGUAUGUACCUGUGUUGCCAUAUACUAGAUAUAUGGUAUGUCUGUUGCCAUGAAGUUAGAAACCCAAAGCAGGGUCAGUGAACUUCACUUCUUUGUCUUUAUUCAGGGUUCUGACUCCCUUGCGGACAAUACUUGUUUAUGUCAUGUAGAGCAGAAUAUCCCCCCGCCUCAAGCUCAAUGUGGGCUGGGUUUGGGUUCCAGCUCCAUUACCAGCCGGGUGACUGUGUGCUACUAAGGUCCAUCCCUUGGAAAGGAGUGAGAGCCUUCAGAACUGGUAUUGGCCUCAGCCUCAGCCCUGCCUGGUGGGGCUUCCUGAAGCAUUUCUUACUCUUGCAGACUCUGGCUCUGAGAGUAGAGCCAAUCACAGGACUCUCUUGUUGCCUAGUUUGAAUGUGUGUAGGAUUUUGUAACUUCAACAUUCUGGGUUUUUUUUUUUUUUUUUUUUUUUUUUUUGAGAAGGAGUCUCGCUCUUUCACCCAGGCUGGAGUGCAGUGGAGCGAUCUCGGCUCACUGCAGGCUCCGCCCCCCGGGAUUCACGCCAUUCUCCUGCCUCAGCCUCCCGCGUAGCUGGGACUACAGGCUCCCGCCACCUCGCCCGGCUAAUUUUUUGUAUUUUUAGUAGAGACGGGGGUUUCACCGUGUUAGCCAGGAUGGUCUCGAUCUCCUGACCUCGUGAUCCGCCCGCCUCGGCCUCCCAAAGUGCUGGGAUUACAAGCGUGAGCCACCGCGCCCGGCCUACAUUCUGUAUUUUAAUAGUUCAAAGCUGCCGCCUUUUGCUUUGUUUAGCAGUUAGAUACAUUGGUGACACAGGGCAUCAUCUGGCUUGCAGGAUCUCGUGUGGAUUUUCUUUCCUACGCUGGAAACUACUAAACUCUAGCUAUUCAGAUGCCACUUCAUAUUCUAAAAUCCAAAUCAAAUAGAAAUAAACAGUACUGUAUGGCAAAGGUGUACCUCACCGAGAACUCAGGUCCACUGAGCCCCCAGCGUAGAUAGACAUUCCACCUCCCAGAUGGUGGAAAAAAGGAUUGAUGGCUGGUUCUGCUCCACCCUCAGAGACUGUGCCAGAACACCUUCUACCCUGGAUAUAACUUUUUUAAGUUUCCAGAACAAUGUAUGUGGUAAAUAUACAUCUAUUCUCAAAUUAGAUGUUUAAAAAUAAAAACCCAAAGUAAGAUUUGACUGUAACAGAAUAGACGGUGCCUUCCUGUUAAAUCAUUCAUAUGUUCCUAGUUAGAUGGAUUUGCCUGUGUCCCAGGACUUUAUAUCUCCUUCAGUUUAAGUUUUGUAUUUUUGCUAUCUGCCAUAGUGCCUGACACUCAGAAAUGUUCCCUUUGUAUAUGAAUUGAUUUAGUUGUGGAUUCUAGUAAGUUACAUACAAGGUUUCUAUAAUGUGGUAAGAAUUUUACAAAUAUACACGAGCUUAGACAUUUCAAUACAAUGUCCUUCAAUGCUGUACAUCCAUUUCAAUGUGAUGCUCCCCUUAAUCAAAGCAUUUUAGGAACUCCAAUCUGAAAAUGGUCUUCACAUAAAUUCUUAAGGACCAAGCAGCUGGAACAACACCACCACCACCAAAAGCGAAAAACAGGUUUUAUUCUGAACUAAAUUUUUUCCAAAAACCUAACAUUUGAGAUUAGCCAAUUAUGUCGUAUUCUUAAAUCAAAUUAGGUAUCAUAUUUGGACUCAAAUGCCUUGUGGCUGUUUCUAAAAUUUGAAACUAUGUUGAAAGGAAAAAGAUGCAAUUCUGAAAGAGAAUUUCCAUGUCCAUUUUAAGUGACAGCAGCAGAGAGAAAUAUACAGACCCCCAGGAGGACAGCUUUGAAAAGUAAAAUGCCCAUUUGGAUGUGUAAAUUAUCGCUUGAUUGUAAUGGCAAUAAUUCAUACUUAAUUGCCUCCAGUUUUUUUUGUAGGUUAAUGACACUAGGAUAGUUAUAGGUCAGCUGACAGCCGGUUAACAGAGGGAUCUAUGCUUCCUUGCACCUCUCUGAGAGUAUGGUUAUACUUCUAUACGGGCUUGAGGGUCUCAGAUACUAAGGCUACUCAUUCAAUGCCUUCACUUCCUCAGACAGUGGUUUUCUAAAAUAGAAUGUCUCUUCUUGGGCUUCCUCUUAGGAACAAGGGAGAAGGCCAAGACUUUAAAAUCUGCACUUCUCAAAUGCAUACAUGAAGCCAGUGGGGUUUAGGCAGUUCUCUUUGUCCUAAGCUUGAGAGAGAGUGUAGAUUUCCCUCCUGGUCAACUUCUAGUCCCUUCUUCCUAACCUGAAGUCCUACUUCUGUGUCUGAUAAGCGGAAUCAAGUGACUGAGAAUUCUGCUACUCUUUUAGCCCUGUGACCUUGAAUAAAACGUUUAAUCUCUCUAAGCCUAUUUUCCUAUCUGUAAAAUGGAGGAUUUACUUCCUUUCAGGGUUGUUUUGUGGAUUGAACAACCGUGAUGUUUUAUGUGGAUGAAUGUAAAACACCUAGAAUAAUGAAUGGCACGUAAAAUAUGUUAAAUAAAUGUUAGAUGGCUUUCUGUCCCCUCUA